AGUGUGCUGAGCUCUCCGCGUCGCCUCUGUCGCCCGCGCCUGGCCUACCGCGGCACUCCCGGCUGCACGCUCUGCUUGGCCUCGCCAUGCCGGUGGACCUCAGCAAGUGGUCCGGGCCCUUGAGCCUGCAAGAAGUGGACGAGCAGCCGCAGCACCCGCUGCAUGUCACCUACGCCGGGGCGGCGGUGGACGAGCUGGGCAAAGUGCUGACGCCCACCCAGGUUAAGAAUAGACCCACCAGCAUUUCGUGGGAUGGUCUUGAUUCAGGGAAGCUCUACACCUUGGUCCUGACAGACCCGGAUGCUCCCAGCAGGAAGGAUCCCAAAUACAGAGAAUGGCAUCAUUUCCUGGUGGUCAACAUGAAGGGCAAUGACAUCAGCAGUGGCACAGUCCUCUCCGAUUAUGUGGGCUCGGGGCCUCCCAAGGGCACAGGCCUCCACCGCUAUGUCUGGCUGGUUUACGAGCAGGACAGGCCGCUAAAGUGUGACGAGCCCAUCCUCAGCAACCGAUCUGGAGACCACCGUGGCAAAUUCAAGGUGGCGUCCUUCCGUAAAAAGUAUGAGCUCAGGGCCCCGGUGGCUGGCACGUGUUACCAGGCCGAGUGGGAUGACUAUGUGCCCAAACUGUACGAGCAGCUGUCUGGGAAGUAGGGGGUUAGCUUGGGGACCUGAACUGUCCUGGAGGCCCCAAGCCAUGUUCCCCAGUUCAGUGUUGCAUGUAUAAUAGAUUUCUCCUCUUCCUGCCCCCCUUGGCAUGGGUGAGACCUGACCAGUCAGAUGGUAGUUGAGGGUGACUUUUCCUGCUGCCUGGCCUUUAUAAUUUUACUCACUCACUCUGAUUUAUGUUUUGAUCAAAUUUGAACUUCAUUUUGGGGGGUAUUUUGGUACUGUGAUGGGGUCAUCAAAUUAUUAAUCUGAAAAUAGCAACCCAGAAUGUAAAAAAGAAAAAACUGGGGGGAAAAAGACCAGGUCUACAGUGAUAGAGCAAAGCAUCAAAGAAUCUUUAAGGGAGGUUUAAAAAAAAAAAAAAAAAAAAAGAUUGGUUGCCUCUGCCUUUGUGAUCCUGAGUCCAGAAUGGUACACAAUGUGAUUUUAUGGUGAUGUCACUCACCUAGACAACCAGAGGCUGGCAUUGAGGCUAACCUCCAACACAGUGCAUCUCAGAUGCCUCAGUAGGCAUCAGUAUGUCACUCUGGUCCCUUUAAAGAGCAAUCCUGGAAGAAGCAGGAGGGAGGGUGGCUUUGCUGUUGUUGGGACAUGGCAAUCUAGACCGGUAGCAGCGCUCGCUGACAGCUUGGGAGGAAACCUGAGAUCUGUGUUUUUUAAAUUGAUCGUUCUUCAUGGGGGUAAGAAAAGCUGGUCUGGAGUUGCUGAAUGUUGCAUUAAUUGUGCUGUUUGCUUGUAGUUGAAUAAAAAUAGAAACCUGAAUGAA